GCUCUAGGGGCUGGACUCAGGGCGGUUUGAAAGAUCGGCGCGCACCGCAGGAGCAACGGUUGGUCCUGCGGCUGUGAUGUCGGUGUUGAGGCCCCUGGACAAGCUGCCCGGCCUGAACACGGCCACCAUCUUGCUGGUGGGCACGGAGGAUGCUCUUCUGCAGCAGCUGGCGGACUCGAUGCUCAAAGAGGACUGCGCCUCCGAGCUGAAGGUCCACUUGGCAAAGUCCCUCCCUUUGCCCUCCAGUGUGAAUCGGCCCCGAAUUGACCUGAUCGUGUUUGUGGUUAAUCUUCACAGCAAAUACAGUCUCCAGAACACAGAGGAGUCCCUGCGCCAUGUGGAUGCCAGCUUCUUCUUGGGGAAGGUGUGUUUCCUCGCCACAGGUGCUGGGCGGGAGAGCCACUGCAGCAUUCACCGGCACACCGUGGUGAAGCUGGCCCACACCUAUCAAAGCCCCCUGCUCUACUGUGACCUGGAGGGUCUCCCAAGCUGGAAACCUGGGGGUCGGCCUUGCUCCCCUCACUCCAUGGCCAGCCGCUGCAUCAUCCCCUGCCCUGGGCCACCUGCCCUGGACGUGGGCCACAGUGCCAGAGAGAGGGACCCUUGCAGACCUCAGUCCAUCUGGCAAACACUUCACCAUCGCCCUCUCCAUGAAGCCUUCCGGCCCACCUUCCAGGAUGACGUGAGCUGGUGCCCUUGCUGCGAGGCUGUCUUCCCCCAUCAGCACAAGUGUGAGAUUCCCUCAGGGCAGACCCACAUGCUACUUGGGCCUGGUACAAGUGUCUGAUGUCAGGCUGGGCACUGUGGCUUCACACCUAUAAUCCCAGCACUUUGGGAGGCCGAGGAGGGCGGAUCACCUGAGGUCAGGAGUUCGAGACCAGCCUGGCCAAAUGGUGAAACCCCACCUCUACUAAAAAUACAAAAAUUAGCCGGGCAUGGUGGUGCAUGCCUGUAAUCCCAGUUACUCGGGAGGCUGAGGCAGGAGAAUCGCUUGAAUCUGGGAGGCAGAGGUUGCAGUGAGCCGAGAUUGCACCACUGCACAGAGCCAGACUCUUUUUCAAAAAAAAAAAAAAAAAAAGCAGGUGUCUGAUAUCCCCAACCAGCUCUGUCCAGGAAGGGCAGGAAGAGAGGAGGAGACAGGUGGGUUGGGGGAGAUGGCAGGGGAGCACUCGGGGUCAUGGAGAGGCUUUGGCUAGACGGAGCAGAGGAACCACUCAGGGUCUGUGUCCUGGCUGCGGGGUCCAUCCCCCUCCCUACCCAAGAGGAGGCUCUGGUCUGCCCCCAGACACCUCCCAGCACCCAGCAGAGGGCCCACCCAGGCGGUGCUGGUUGAGGGGCUGAAUUGGGGAACCACAGGUAGAAAGAGAGGCCAGGCCGGGUGCGGUGGCUCACGCCU